AGACAAGGCCCGGGGGCUCCGCCAGCAGCAGGUCCCUCGGGCCCCAGCCCUCGCUGCCACCCGGGCCUGGAGCCCCACACCCGAGGUAAGCCAGCCCACUUGCCUGUUUCUGGUCCCAGCCCUGGAUGGACGCUCUUGGGCUGGGGGAGAGGACAGGACCACCCCCCUCCUCUCCUUUCUUGCAUCCUCCCUCUCUUGGGCCCUCGGCACAGUUCUCCGCCCCUCCCAGCCCCUCAGUCCCUCUUGUCGCUUGUUGGACUGUGCUGGCCUUGCCGGCCCACUGUAAUGUGAGGCUCCCGCUGCCGCUACAGGGUGCAGACUGGCUGCCAAGGCCACACUUUUGGCUAAAAGAGGCACUGCCAGGUGUACAGUCCUGGGCAUGCGCUGUUUGAGCUUCGGGGGAGAGCCCAGCACUGGUCCCCGGAAAGGUGCCUAGAAGAACAAGGUGCAGGACCCCGUGGUGAGUAGCGGGCUGGUGGAUGGGGAGGCAAGGGCCAGAGAACCAAAUGGCCCUAGACCACAAGGAGGUAGGAGGCAGGGCCUGAGCUGCCCUCAAGAGACCUGCUCCCGGGCUCCCCCUAGCGCAGAGGGCUCCUAAGGCUGCCCUGCCUGCCUUUCCCUCCAUCACGGACAACAGUCACUGGCCUGGCUCGGAGGCCUUGAUUCCACUUAGCCAAGAGGCACACACCAGGACCUGGAGGACAACCCCGGGAAGGCCUGGGGGUCUGUUCCACAGGUGUGCAGGCAUUCUGUGUGCUAAAGGAUGGGGAUGAGGGUGGUAGCUGGGACCCAAGAGGAGGCUGGCUAAUGAGGACUUACGAAGGCUCUAGGGCCCCAAAAGGGUGUUUGGGAGUGCUAGCAGUGGGAGCUCAGGAAGGCUGGCUGGGAUCAGGAACGAUGGCUCAAGGGGGAAACUUCUAGGAGCAUGACUAGGCUGCCAGAUCCAUAGGAGGCUGGGAGGGGGACAGACCUAGACCAGCUCCCAGGGUGGCUCAGCUCUCAGAGACCAGGCUGGUAUGGAAGCCUAGCUGGCCCUCCUGGGAGUGGCUCAGGCCUGAGUGUAGCUGAGGGGAUGGAAAAGCCCACCCUGCUUGGAAUCUGCAGGCUUGGCAGACUCUGCCCCCUUGUGGCCACAGGAAGCCAUGACCCAGGCCCCAUGUUUUCAGAGGGCCCAUUAGCUCCCACCAUCCCCCGGCUCUGUGGUCAUCGAGGGACACCUAUAGUCAGAGGAGAGAACUCAGGUGGCUCUGGGUCCAGAACACAGUUCACAGAGGGGCGAGGUGAAGCAGCUCUGGGUGGGCAGCACAGGCUGAGGCUUGGGGCUCACUAUCAUUAGAUAACUCUUAGAGUGACCAGCUAGCACCCUAAUUCUUCUCCAGCCCUCAGCUUCCUCUCCGGCAGCCUGGGGUGAAGGCCUCUGUAGGACCAAGUGUGUCCAGCUAUAACUCCUUCCAGCCACUUCUGGCAUCUCCAGACCUACAACGCAGAGCAGGAAGGUUCUGGGAAAAGAGGACCCCUCUCUCCCCUCCAGCUGUGUGACCUUGUAACCUUAGACAACCUCUGAGCUUCUCUGAGCCUUGUUUGCUCAUCUGGAAAAAGGGGAUUAAACCAUUUACCUCAUGGAGUUGUGAAAGAAUAGCUGCAAAGCACCUAACACAUAGUAAGGUUCCCAGUGCAGCUACUUCUGCUGGGUUGAGUCUAGCUGUGUAGGCCCCUUGUUCCUCACCUGGAGAAACUGGGGUGGCAGGCCGGUCCCCCACAAAAGAUAACUCAUCUCUUAAUUUGCAAGCUGCCUCAACAGGAGGGUGGGGGAACAGCUCAACAAUGGCUGAUGGGCGCUCCUGGUGUUGAUAGAGAUGGAACUUGGACUUGGAGGCCUCUCCACGCUGUCCCACUGCCCCUGGCCUAGGCAGCAGGCUCCACUUGGUCUCUCCGCGCAGCCUGCCCUGUGGCCCACCCUGGCCGCUCUGGCUCUGCUGAGCAGCGUCGCAGAGGCCUCCCUGGGCUCCGCGCCCCGCAGCCCUGCCCCCCGCGAAGGCCCCCCGCCUGUCCUGGCGUCCCCCGCCGGCCACCUGCCGGGGGGACGCACGGCCCGCUGGUGCAGUGGAAGAGCCCGGCGGCCGCCGCCGCAGCCUUCUCGGCCCGCGCCCCCGCCGCCUGCACCCCCAUCUGCUCUUCCCCGCGGGGGCCGCGCGGCGCGGGCUGGGGGCCCGGGCAGCCGCGCUCGGGCAGCGGGGGCGCGGGGCUGCCGCCUGCGCUCGCAGCUGGUGCCGGUGCGCGCGCUCGGCCUGGGCCACCGCUCCGACGAGCUGGUGCGUUUCCGCUUCUGCAGCGGCUCCUGCCGCCGCGCGCGCUCUCCACACGACCUCAGCCUGGCCAGCCUACUGGGCGCCGGGGCCCUGCGACCGCCCCCGGGCUCCCGGCCCGUCAGCCAGCCCUGCUGCCGACCCACGCGCUACGAAGCGGUCUCCUUCAUGGACGUCAACAGCACCUGGAGAACCGUGGACCGCCUCUCCGCCACCGCCUGCGGCUGCCUGGGCUGAGGGCUCGCUCCAGGGCUUUGCAGACUGGACCCUUACCGGUGGCUCUUCCUGCCUGGGACCCUCCCGCAGAGUCCCACUAGCCAGCGGCCUCAGCCAGGGACGAAGGCCUCAAAGCUGAGAGGCCCCUGCCGGUGGGUGAUGGAUAUCAUCCCCGAACAGGUGAAGGGACAACUGACUAGCAGCCCCAGAGCCCUCACCCUGCGGAUCCCAGCCUAAAAGACACCAGAGACCUCAGCUAUGGAGCCCUUCGGACCCACUUCUCACAGACUCUGGCACUGGCCAGGCCUCGAACCUGGGACCCCUCCUCUGAUGAACACUACAGUGGCUGAGGCAUCAGCCCCCGCCCAGGCCCUGUAGGGACAGCAUUUGAAGGACACAUAUUGCAGUUGCUUGGUUGAAAGUGCCUGUGCUGGAACUGGCCUGUACUCACUCAUGGGAGCUGGCCCCUAUUUAUUAUUUCUAAGUUAUUUAUUUA